GUUGGCAUUGGGACUGACUCCAGCCUCUGCUCCGGGAGGCCCUCCCGGGCUGCCUGACCUCCCGGGACCAUGCAGAAGGCCUCCCACAAAAACAAAAAAGAAAGAGGAGUCAGCAACAAGGUCAAAACAUCUGUACACAACUUGAGCAAAACACAGCAGACCAAACUCACUGUGGGUAGCCUGGGAUUAGGCCUCAUCAUCAUCCAGCAUGGACCCUACCUCCAGAUCACCCACCUCAUCAGGAAGGGGGCUGCAGCCAACGACGGGAAACUCCAGCCAGGCUGUACAGGAAGCAUGGCUGGGGAGGCCUCAGGAAACUUACAAUCAUGGCAGAAGGUGAAGAGGAAGGAGGUGAUGUUCUGAUUAGUGUUGGCCAUGCCAAUGUGUUAGGAUAUACUCUUCGAGAAUUUUUACAGCUUUUGCAACAUAUCACUAUUGGAACAGUGCUACAAAUCAAGGUUUACCGAGAUUUUAUUAACAUUCCUGAAGAAUGGCAAGAAAUAUAUGAUUUAAUCCCUGAGGCCAAAUUCCCAGUAACAAGCACACCAAAGAAAAUUGAGCUGGCAAAAGAUGAAUCUUUCACAAGCAGUGAUGAUAAUGAAAAUGUAGAUUUAGAUAAAAGACUUCAAUAUUAUAGAUAUCCGUGGUCAACUGUGCAUCACCCUGCAAGGAGACCAAUAUCCAUCUCCAGAGACUGGCAUGGAUAUAAGAAGAAGAACCAUACUAUUAGUGUAGGAAAAGACAUUAAUUGUGACGUGAUGAUUCACAGAGACGACAAGAAAGAAGUGAGGGCCCCUUCUCCAUACUGGAUAAUGGUGAAGCAAGACAAUGAAAGCUCUUCCUCCUCUACCUCCUCUACCUCAGAUGCAUUUUGGCUGGAAGAUUGUGCCCAAGUUGAAGAGGGUAAAGCCCAACUGGUAUCAAAGGUUGGUUAGCAAAUCUGUGGUCAUAUGAGCAUUUAUCUUGCAGACACCCAAGUUUUGUGCCUCACCAGGCACAAGUUUGCUGUACUUAUCAAGGACUGUCUGUAGACUCACCAAUUCUCUUCUCUUAUGACUGCGUUAUAAAGCCUUUAGAGAUGUUCUUCAACAGGAUUAUCUAAAGACUUCCUUGGGUUCUUGCAGGCCUCACAAAUCUUAUUUUCAGAAUAAGACCCUCCUUUUUGAGAAGAAUUUCUUUCUUUUAGAAAAUGCCGUAGAGAAAUCCAAUAUCAGAAUGUCUGAACAUAGUAGAGAAUGUCACUUUAUGUAAACACUACAUUUUUCUUUAAAUAUUUAGUUUCUCUCUUUUUUUUGGUAAACUUCAAGUACUAUAAUUAAAAUAACUAAGAGACAUAA